AGGAAGCCGAGGUCUGAAUUGCGCGUGGUGGCCAUGGCGGCCAGCGGGGCUGUGGAACCAGGGCCCCCGGGGGCUGCCGUCGCCCCGUCGCCCGCCCCGGCCCCGCCGCCUGCCCCUGAUCACCUGUUCCGGCCCAUCAGCGCCGAGGACGAGGAGCAGCAGCCCACCGAGAUCGAGUCGCUAUGCAUGAACUGUUACUGCAAUGGCAUGACGCGCCUCCUGCUCACCAAGAUUCCCUUCUUCAGAGAAAUAAUAGUGAGCUCCUUUUCCUGCGAGCACUGUGGCUGGAACAACACGGAGAUCCAGUCGGCAGGCAGGAUCCAGGACCAGGGAGUGCGCUACACUUUGUCUGUCAGGGCUCUGGAGGACAUGAACAGAGAAGUGGUGAAGACUGACUCUGCUGCCACAAGGAUUCCUGAGCUAGAUUUUGAAAUUCCUGCCUUUAGCCAGAAAGGAGCUCUGACCACUGUUGAAGGAUUGAUCACCCGUGCUAUCUCUGGCCUGGAGCAGGACCAGCCUGCACGAAGGGCAAACAAAGAUGCUACAGCUGAAAGAAUUGAUGAGUUCAUUGUCAAACUGAAGGAGCUAAAGCAAGUAGCCUCCCCUUUCACUCUGAUCAUUGAUGAUCCCUCAGGGAACAGUUUUGUGGAAAACCCACAUGCUCCUCAGAAAGAUGAUGCCCUGGUGAUCACACACUACAACCGGACCCGACAGCAGGAAGAGAUGCUGGGGCUUCAAGAAGAAGCACCAGCAGAGAAGCCAGAAGAGGAAGAUCUCAGAAAUGAAGUGCUCCAGUUCAGCACAAACUGCCCAGAAUGCAAUGCCCCCGCUCAGACCAACAUGAAGCUAGUACAAAUCCCUCACUUUAAGGAGGUUAUCAUCAUGGCUACCAACUGCGAGAACUGUGGGCAUCGGACCAAUGAGGUGAAAUCUGGAGGAGCAGUAGAACCCUUGGGCACCAGGAUCACCCUCCACAUCACAGAUGCCUCAGAUAUGACCAGAGACCUCCUCAAGUCUGAGACUUGCAGUGUGGAAAUCCCAGAGCUAGAAUUUGAACUGGGAAUGGCAGUCCUCGGGGGCAAGUUCACCACACUGGAAGGGCUGCUGAAAGACAUCCGGGAACUGGUGACCAAAAAUCCUUUCACACUGGGCGACAGUUCCAAUCCUGGACAGACGGAGAGACUACAGGAGUUUAGCCAGAAGAUGGACCAGAUCAUCGAAGGUAACAUGAAGGCCCACUUUAUUAUGGAUGAUCCAGCAGGAAACAGUUACUUGCAGAAUGUGUAUGCGCCUGAAGAUGAUCCUGAGAUGAAGGUGGAGCGUUACAAGCGCACCUUUGACCAAAAUGAGGAGCUAGGGCUCAAUGACAUGAAGACAGAGGGCUAUGAGGCAGGCCUGGCUCCGCAACGGUAGCAGUGGGUGGCUCAAGGGCCAGCCUCCAGCGCUGCUCUUUCUGUAGGUUAUUUAUUAGUAUUGGAUGAAGGCGAAGGCUGGGAGUGUCUUUCCCACCAGCCCUUGCCCAUGGUGGGGAGGACAUCUGGUCUGAGUCAGAGAUCUGUGCACACUUUCUAAACAGCUUGUGAUGCAAGUGUGAGCCUAUUGUGUUACUUGACCUUAUUUUGGAAGUUUUGAAUUGGCCUAGGAGGAAACCCAGAAAUGAACCAGGGGUAUGUCAUCACUUUUUUCAUAUCAAGUCCUCACCCUCCUUCCACAUAAUGCUCUAUCCUCUAAGGUUGGAACUCUGAAGUUGGAGAAGGUGGAAUAAAGUUACACCUGGAGUUUGUUGUUGGUUUUGAGUAUAUAAAAUACUGACUUUGAACAGGAAAGGAGUCUCCUGAGGGGAGACCGAGUCCAGCACAAGUGAAGGAGUUACCAUUGAAAUGAUGACUUUCAAACAGCACUGGCCUCUGUAUUGACCCUAUCCUUGUUUGAUAUCAUGCUGUUAGAAUUCAGCCUCCUAAAGAAAAUUUUCCCGUGUAUCUACUGUAAUUUGGGGAUUGCAGCUGGCAUUUAAUUCAUUCCUUCAGCAGAUGCUUGCUUAUCUACUUUAUGCCAAGCACACCACAGAACAGAGGACAAAAUAAAUCUCUUUCAUGGAACUUGAAGUCUAGUGGGGAAAAAUGACAAUAAACAGAUCAGGAAAACAGUACAUCAGAUGGUGAUUAGUGUCAUGGAGGAAUGUAAAGCAGGGAAUGGGGCUGGGUUGUGCAAGGAAAUGGGGAGUAGGGAAGAUCUUCUGAACAAGAAGGUGAUAAUUUGACAUUUGGGCAAAGCUGAGGAGGAGGUCAGGGAGUGAGCUGUGUGGGUAUCUGGGGGAAGAGAUUUCCUGGCAGAGGGAACUGCAAAUGCUAGAGCUGUGAGGUUAGAGCCAGUGGGGGUACCUGAUCAGUUAGCCCUACUCUCAGUUAGAAAUGUUGAAACACAUUCAUCCAGAGAGAAAGGAGGCUCUCUGCAGUUCUUCUGAAAGUUAAGGACCAGUGAACACUCUGCUGCUUGGGCCCUGGACUUCCCAGCCAGUGUUCUUUGCACUGUAGUCUCCUGCCUCUCAUAAACAAAAGGUGACUCCUGUGGUGCAGACUGCAGGGUAUUUGUUCAAUAAAGACCAGUUCAUUGAUUAAGAUGUUAUCACAAACCUUAUUGCUUUGUGUUGCAAACUUUUUUUUUUUUUUUUUUUGGUAGAGACAGAGUCUCGCGCUGUUGCCCAGGCUGGAGUGCAGUGGUGUGAUCUUGGCUUAUUGCAACCUUUGCCUCCCGGGUUUAAGCAAUUCUGCCUCAGCCUCCCGAGUAGCGGGGACUACAGGCGCACGCCGCCACACCCAGCUAAUUUCUUUUGUAUUUUAGUAGAGACGGGGUUUCACCGUGUUGCCCAGGCUGGUCUCGAACUCCUGAGCUCAGGCAAUCCGCCAGCCUUGGCCUCCCAAAGUGCUAGGAUUACAGGCGUGAGCUACCGCGUCCGGCUGUGUUGCAAACUUAACUCUGAAGAAUGAGUUAGAGAUGAUUUAGCAAUCAGACAUCUACUCUCGUUGCUCUGUUAAACUACUCUCAAAGGUCACAAGUGAUUUUCCACUUGGAAAGUGUUAUCUAUUUCUGUCACAUUUGAUAGUGGACCAUCUCUUCUUAACCCUUCUUUUGGCUCUCGAGAUACUGUACCCUUGGUUUUCCCUUCACUUUGAAUAUUUCUUAUUUGGACACUUUGCCUCCUCCCCUCUUACUAAAUUUGUUUCUGAGAGUUCUGCUUUCAGACAUCUCUCCAUAUCAGAUUCUUUGGCAUCUUACUAUCAUGUGGGACUAACUUCCAUACCUGUAUCUCUAAUUUCUGUAAGUGAGGGCGAGAGUAAGGUGUUUGGAGACUCAGGUUAGCAAAUGACUCAUUCAAACUAUAAAGCUUCAGUACUUUGGGCAAACUUCUCACAGGCAACUAUUCUACCCUAAGAGAUUAUCUCUAGGUAUGUUUCCAGCUGACUUGGGAAUCUAAGUUUACCAGACAACCCUCUGAUCUAUCAUUUGGUCUCUUAAGUAGACUUCCCCAUAGUGUAGGUGUGCUCUGUUAAGAUAAACUGCAGUAUCAGGUUCAUUUUCCAUUGUGAAGGAAAAAAAAUGGCACUCUGGCUUAUUACUGAAUCUCUUGUGAGUUUGGUUGGUGUGAGGCAAUCUCCCAGAAUCCACCCAGUUCCUAGGAAAUGAUGACCUGAGUUUCUGAACUUGAAGACUGAGGACCAGGUGCCAGACUGGGAUAACCCAGCUAAGGUACUUCCUGCCCUUUGAUGACAAGGCAUUCUUCAGUUUCAUACCCUUCUCUUGAAUUAUCUUUCAGCUCCUUUCUCAUUUCAUAAAGUGUGUCAGGAUGGGAGCUUACAUAUAGUUAACUGAGUCUUGCUCCACAGCACCCAGCAUAUGACACAUGGUUAAUAAAAUCUGUUAAAAUCCUCCAUCAUAGAUUAAACCCUAUUAGGACACUAGGGAUAACAUCUAUAGGUAAAAAGAUAGGGAAAGGGUCUCGCUUUAAGGCCAGGGUAGGUGAGUCAAAGUGCCAGGAACAUGUGGAUUCAGUUUCACAGCCAUGAGUAACAUUUAAGUGGAAAAGGUUUGUGAUUGUGUUAAAAAAGGAAAGUGGUUCAUGCAUGAGGGCACGCCUCCUACUUUCAUGGGUCAAGUAUGUGAAAUGCAGCCAUGUUCGGUCAUUAGACGUGUGGACGAACAUACAGGUAGGUACUGAAUGUACAUCUGUGUCAUGAUGAGUGGAGGAGGGGAGGUGAGUGUUGGGAGCAAGUAUGAAGGGCAGUUGACUUGGCCAACUGAAAACUUUAAUGAUGGCAACACUUUCAUUCUAACAUCAGUAUAUUUCCUUCUUUGUACACCUGUGGUAUGUGCCUGAUGCACACUGCAGAAAAUGGUGUCUCUGCUUACAUUUAGGGCAGUGGUGGCUAAGACUACUUGGCUUUAUUCCUAUUAAAAAAUGUUUUUUACACACUUCUUUUUAAGGCAAAUGGCAGUGUUUCCAACUGUGGAGAGAAAAAGCUGCUUAUUUUGUGCGUUCACCUCAGUUUAGUAUUGGCACUUCCAAUGCUUGUUUUCCUAGUCUGUAAAAUGGGGAUAAUUAGGAUAAACAAAAUUAUCCCCAUUUUACAGGUGACAAAACAGCCUCAGAGAGGUUACUUCCAGAAGGAAGCAGAGCUUUUUUUUUUUUUUUUUUUUUUUUUUUUUUUUUUUGAGACGGAGUCUCACUCUGUUGCCCAGACUGGAGUGCAGUGGCGUGAUCUUGGCUCACCACAACCUCUGCCUCCCAGGUUCAAGCGAUUCUCUUGCCUCAGCCUUCUGAGUAGCUGGGACUACAGGUGCACGCCACCAUGCCUGGCUAAUUUUUUUUUUUUUUUUUUUUUUGGAGACAGUCUUGCUCUGUCACCCAGGAUGGAGUGCAGUGGUGCGAUCUUGGCUCACUGCAGCCUUGCCUCCUGGGUUCAAGCAAUUCUCCUGCCUCAGCCUCCUGAGUAGCUGGGAUUACAGACGCCCACCACUGCACCCAGCUAAUUUUUGUAUUUUUAGUAGAGAUGGGGUUUCACCAUGUUGGUCAGGCUGGUCUCAAACCCCUGACCUCGUGAUCCACCUGCCUUGGCCUCCCAAAGUGCAGGGAUUACAGGCGUGAGCCACCGUGCCUGGCCAGAAGUAGAGCUUCUAAGAGGCAGGUGUCAAACCCAUGCCAGUCAGACUCUGAAACCUGAGGUCUGAAUAUUUUAAGCUCAGCUCCACAAUUACUGUAUUUGUUCUAUUAGAUACAACUGCAGAGAGAGGCCAAAGCUCAGAGCAGGCCAUUGGCACGGCAUCUGAUCCUGCUUAACUGCCCUGCAGCACAGGGUGGAGACACUUGGGCCUUGUCAGGCUAAGGGACUGGGGUAGGAUGGGUAGCAGUGGAAUUGAAGACAAAGAAAACAAAUGGGCAGAAGAUGGGUGGGUGGAAGUUCAGAGGGCUAUCCUGGCAGUGUUCACUGGAGCAGAAGUGUGAGGCUUUCUGAAUGCCUGCUGACACCAGGGUGGGGCAGGGCUGUGUAGUGUGAGAUGCACCAAAUUGGACGAGAAGCCAAGGCAGGCUUGUGUAUGGGGUACCCUGGGGCCCUCCGCCUAGUGAAGCCCUAUCUUCUCAGCCCAGCGUCCUCGUCUCACAAGCCCUCAGAGCCCCAGCCUGCUUUCCUUUCUGGGCCUGUGCUGCAACCCCCUCAACAUGGCCCACUGGGUAAAAAUUCAUGCUUCAAGACUGAUCCCCAAGCCUGUUUUGUAUUAUAUGAGUAAAGAAUUUUUUAAACACUUAUCCCCAGAUAAUGUGUAUUUAUUUAUAAAGUAUAGCCCUGUCUGCUUGACUAAUAUAUUAAAAAAGUGACCUUUUUGACUCUUGGUCCAAGAAACUAUUGUUUGCACUUUUGUGUAGUUGUGUAUAGCAUCCUGCAAAUUCUGUCAGAAGUCUGUGAUUUCAGUAACACUAAAACUUCUCUCUCAAAUGGUACAAGUUUUCAGUUUUAAGACAAGUUCUGGGAAUCUAAUGUACAACAUGUUGACUAUAGCUAAUAAUUCUGUAUUGUUUACUUGAAGUUUGCUAAGACAAAUUUGCUUAAGUGCCCCCCCACCGAACUACUACAUAAAUUAGUGAAGGAUGUUUUACUUAAUUUGAUUUUGGUAAUCAUUACACAAUGUAUAAUUAUAUCCAGUCAUCACAUUGUACACCUUGAAUAUAUAUAAUUUUUUGUCAAAUAAUAAAGCUGGGAAGAAAACGAUAAAACUGACAAUCUAACAUAUAUGAUGAGGUAAAAAGAUCUGGUAUUUCAAGAAAUUUGGAUGACCUCUUGCACCCCACUUCGCUAGCCUCUACUCCCUAGAGUCAUGUUCUGACUAUGUGAAGUUGAGCAACUUCCUUAAUCUUGCCACGCUUCAGUUCUUAUCUGUAAAAUAUGAUAAUGAAACGAUUUGAGAAUUGUGAGGGUUAAAUGAGAUAAUUCAGGUAAAGCUCUAAACCCCCUGCAAAGAAUAAAGUCUUUUCUUUCCCCCCAAAA